AAGUGAUGCCUAAAGCUGUGGACCGCGUGGGCUCGCCUCCCUGGGACUAGGUUUCAGCGGCCGCUGCGAUGACCAAAAUAAAGGCAGAUCCCGACGGGCCCGAGGCUCAGGCGGAGGCGUGUUCCGGGGAGCGCACCUACCAGGAGCUGCUGGUCAACCAGAACCCCAUCGCGCAGCCCCUGGCUUCUCGCCGCCUCACGCGGAAGCUCUACAAAUGCAUCAAGAAAGCGGUGAAGCAGAAGCAGAUUCGGCGCGGGGUGAAAGAGGUUCAGAAAUUUGUCAACAAAGGAGAAAAAGGGAUCAUGGUUUUGGCAGGAGACACACUGCCCAUUGAGGUAUACUGCCAUCUCCCAGUCAUGUGUGAGGACCGAAAUUUGCCCUAUGUCUAUAUCCCCUCUAAGACGUUCCCAUCUUGUAAAGUGGGAAUCCCAGCCCAGGCGCUGUGGCUCACACCUGUAAUCCUAGUGCUUUGGGAGGCCAAGACAGGAGGAUCAGUUGAGGACAGGAGUUCAGGAAUAACCUGCGCAACAAAGACCUGGGUGCAGCCGCAGGCUCCAAGCGCCCCACCUGUGUGAUAAUGGUCAAGCCCCAUGAGGAGUACCAGGAGGCUUACGAUGAGUGCCUGGAGGAGGUGCAGUCCCUGCCCCUACCCCUAUGAGGGGCUCCGGUAGCACCUGGGCACCUGCCGCUGGAAGCUAUUGGGCUGGCAGCAGGACGACUGGCUGUCCUCCUGCCCACCCACACUGACGGCAUCUUCCCAGUUCCCCAAGGCACGCCUUCUUCCCAGGCAGCUCUAACAGCCCUUUCAUGAAGGUAAUGCUAGUCUUCUGUCCAUCAGUGCCAUUUCCUGUAGAACUAAAGGCUGUUCCAAGAAUGUGGGGUGGGGAAAGUAAAUGCUAAGACUAAAA